GGGCUCCGAGCACUUCCGGAGCCGGGCGCGGGGCCGAGGGCUGGGCCCCCCUCUUCCCUUCCCUCCUCCAGCGGCUGCGCUCCCUCCGGCGCCCUCGGCCCCGGGGCGGAGGCGGCCCCCGCCGCUGGGAAGCGAGCGCCGCGGCUCUUUCUACGCGCGCGCGCGCGUUGACCGCCUCGGGGUCGCGGCCCUUGUCCGGGGGUUGCUGGGGUCCUCAGGCCUAUGGCUGCCGAGGCGGGCGUCGUGGGAGCUGGGGCCUCCCCUGAUGGGGAUUGGAGAGACCAGGCCUGUGGGCUUCUGCUACACGUGCAUUUGUCUUCCCGACUGGGUCGCGCAGCCCCUGUACGUACAGGUCGUCAUCUUAGAACAGUGUUUGAAGAUACUGUGGAGGAGCGUGUCAUCAAUGAAGAAUAUAAAAUCUGGAAGAAGAAUACACCGUUUCUAUAUGACCUGGUUAUGACCCAUGCUCUUCAGUGGCCCAGUCUUACCGUUCAGUGGCUUCCUGAAGUGACUAAACCUGAAGGAAAAGAUUAUGCCCUUCAUUGGCUAGUGCUGGGGACUCAUACGUCUGAUGAGCAGAAUCAUCUGGUGGUUGCUCGAGUACAUAUUCCCAAUGAUGAUGCACAGUUUGAUGCUUCCCAUUGUGACAGUGACAAGGGUGAAUUUGGUGGCUUUGGUUCUGUAACAGGAAAAAUUGAAUGUGAAAUUAAAAUCAAUCACGAAGGAGAAGUAAACCGUGCUCGUUACAUGCCGCAGAAUCCUCACAUCAUUGCUACAAAAACACCAUCUUCUGAUGUGUUGGUUUUUGACUAUACAAAACACCCUGCUAAACCAGACCCAAGUGGAGAAUGUAAUCCUGAUCUCAGAUUAAGAGGUCACCAGAAGGAAGGCUAUGGUCUCUCCUGGAAUUCAAAUUUGAGUGGACAUCUCCUAAGUGCAUCUGAUGACCAUACUGUUUGUCUGUGGGAUAUAAACGCAGGACCAAAAGAAGGCAAAAUUGUGGAUGCUAAAGCCAUCUUUACUGGCCACUCAGCUGUUGUAGAGGAUGUGGCCUGGCACCUGCUGCACGAGUCAUUGUUUGGAUCUGUUGCUGAUGAUCAGAAACUUAUGAUAUGGGACACCAGGUCCAAUACCACCUCCAAGCCGAGUCACUUGGUGGAUGCGCACACUGCCGAAGUCAACUGCCUCUCAUUCAAUCCCUACAGCGAAUUUAUUCUAGCCACCGGCUCUGCGGAUAAGACCGUAGCUUUAUGGGAUCUGCGUAACUUAAAAUUAAAACUCCAUACCUUCGAAUCUCAUAAAGAUGAAAUUUUCCAGGUAUGUGACAGUUUUCUGGUGUCUGUAUGUCAGGAAAUGAAAUCCAGGGAUUCAUCAGUUAAGCUAUACCAGACUCGUGGGUCCACUAUUGAAAAAAAUGUCUUGUACGUGGUGUUACAUGGAGAUGCUCAUAGGGUCCACUGGUCUCCACAUAAUGAAACUAUUCUGGCUUCAAGUGGUACUGACCGCCGCCUGAAUGUGUGGGAUUUAAGUAAAAUUGGGGAAGAACAAUCAGCAGAAGAUGCAGAAGAUGGGCCUCCAGAACUCCUGUUUAUUCAUGGAGGACACACUGCUAAGAUUUCAGAUUUUAGCUGGAACCCCAAUGAGCCUUGGGUCAUUUGCUCAGUGUCUGAGGAUAACAUCAUGCAGAUAUGGCAAAUGGCUGAAAAUAUUUACAAUGAUGAAGAGUCAGAUGUCACGACAUCCGAACUGGAGGGACAAGGAUCUUAAACCCAAAGUACGAGAAAUGUUUCUGUUGAAUGUAAUGCUACAUGAAUGCUUGAUUUAUCAAGCGCCAAAAAGGCAUUGUAUAGUAGGAAAUGUAAGUGGGGUGGCUUAUGGCUUCUUUAUCCUCUGAUUCUAGCACUUUCAAGUGAGCUGUUGCGUACUGUAUCAUAUUGUAGCUAUUAGGGAAGAGAAGAAUGUUGCUUAAGAAAGAACAUCACCAUUGAUUUUAAAUACAAGUAGCAGGGUAUUGCCUUUGAUUCAACUGUUUUAAGUCCUCAUUUUCUCAAACUAAGUGCUUGCUGUUCCCAAAUAUGCAAGAAUAACUUUUACACUUUUUCCUUCCAACACUUCUUGAUUGGCUUUGCAGAAAUAAAGUUUUAAAAUAAAACUUGUGUUUUUUUAAAAGCUUAGUGGGGGGGGGCGGGGGAGUCUACUUUUUGAGUAGAAAUGGGUAAAAUGGUACCUUUGGACUCCUACAGUUAAGGUCACAUGGAUAAUGAAAGAAUACACAGAAGCUGUUAAGUUUAUCAUACAUAUUUACUUAAUCUAUACAGAAUCAAGUAGAUAAAAUCAGAUUCACAUUAGUGAAAAAUCUCUACAAAAUGUCUUUGAAAAGCAAAACGAGACUGCCUCUUAACAAUUCGUAUCCUCAUGAAAGACGUGGGCUGUAAAAAUAAAGCAGUGUGUUUAGCACAAA